CAAGCCCGGAGGUGGGAACAUCGCAGUGUUCAGAGAACAUCGUGUGUUCAAAGAACCACGUGGGUUCUUUAGGGACAAGAAGGCUGAGAUGGGUAGUGGUGGCAGGAGUGCUCAGGUGUCCACUGGGCAGAGGGCUUGGCUGUUACCCUGCAGAUUUUUGAAAAAUACAAUGUCUAAUGGUUAUGAAGACCACAUGGCCGAAGACUGCAGGGGUGACAUCGGGAGAACGAAUUUGAUCGUCAACUACCUCCCUCAGAACAUGACCCAGGAUGAGUUACGAAGCCUGUUCAGCAGCAUUGGUGAAGUUGAAUCUGCAAAACUUAUUCGGGAUAAAGUAGCAGGACACAGCUUGGGCUAUGGCUUUGUGAACUACGUGACCGCGAAGGAUGCAGAGAGAGCGAUCAACACGCUGAACGGCUUGAGGCUCCAGUCAAAAACCAUUAAGGUGUCGUAUGCUCGCCCGAGCUCAGAGGUGAUCAAAGACGCCAACUUGUACAUCAGCGGGCUCCCGCGGACCAUGACCCAGAAGGACGUAGAAGACAUGUUCUCUCGGUUUGGGCGGAUCAUCAACUCGCGGGUCCUCGUGGAUCAGACUACAGGUUUGUCCAGAGGGGUUGCGUUUAUCCGGUUUGACAAACGGUCGGAGGCAGAAGAGGCAAUUACCAGUUUCAAUGGUCAUAAACCCCCAGGUUCCUCUGAGCCCAUCACAGUGAAGUUUGCAGCCAACCCCAACCAGAACAAAAACGUGGCACUCCUCUCGCAGCUGUACCACUCGCCAGCGCGACGGUUCGGAGGCCCCGUUCACCACCAGGCGCAGAGAUUCAGGUUCUCCCCCAUGGGCGUCGAUCACAUGAGCGGGCUCUCUGGCGUCAACGUGCCAGGAAACGCCUCCUCCGGCUGGUGCAUUUUCAUCUACAACCUGGGGCAGGAUGCCGACGAGGGGAUCCUCUGGCAGAUGUUUGGGCCGUUUGGUGCCGUCACCAAUGUGAAAGUGAUCCGCGACUUCAACACCAACAAGUGCAAAGGGUUUGGCUUUGUGACCAUGACAAACUAUGAAGAAGCCGCGAUGGCCAUAGCCAGCCUGAACGGCUACCGCCUGGGGGACAAAAUCUUACAGGUUUCCUUCAAAACCAACAAGUCCCACAAAUAACUCGCUCAUGCUUUUUUUUGUACGGAAUAGAUAAUUAAGAGUGAAGGAGUUGAAACUUUUCUUGUUAGUGUACAACUCAUUUUGCGCCAAUUUUCACAAGUGUUUGUCUUUGUCUGAAUGAGAAGUGAGAAGGUUUUUAUACUCUGGGAUGCAACCGACAUGUUCAAAUGUUUGAAAUCCCACAAUGUUAGACCAAUCUUAAGUUUCGUAAGUUAUUUCCUUUAAGAUAUAUAUUAAACAGAAAUCUAAGUAGAACUGCAUUGACUAACCAGUCCCUCUGGAUGGUGGUGAACCUGAAGCAUGCUUUAACCUCUAAGACUGUCUAACACGCGUUUCAUUCAAUGUCUCCACAGACUGGGUAGCAAAAAAAUCACCUUUUAGUUUUAGUUUUUAAUCUAAAGAUGUUAGACAGAUGCUGAGUGUGCGUUUUCUCAACCGCUUCAACAUUGUAAGCGAUGUAUGCUUUGGUUGACAGGAAGUUCCUUUUCCAGGCAGGUCCCGUUGCCACCUCCUGCUCACUCAGUCCCGGGCUCUGCCGAGUGGUCCUGGGAAUGGCGGCGGGCCCGUCCAGCGUGGGCCACCACUGGGGCCGGGGGCCACGGGCUGCAUGCUGGGCGGGCCCUCCAGAGAAGGACACAAACGUGUUUCGUAAGCCCAGGCACCAAUGGGAAUGGACCAAAGAGUUUCAGGGAAACUCCAGUAUAUUCCAGAGUCAGAUCUAAGCUCCAGGCACGCCUGAAGAUGUGUUGCUACUCUGACAUCCCGAGUUUCUGUCCACACAUUGCAUGCACAGCGCCCCACACAUUGGAUACUGUUGUUCACGAUAAUUUCUCCCGUUUUCCAGAGCAUUUAACAUAGCUUGGAGGCGUAAAAUGGCUCUGUAUUUUAAUAACACAGAAACAUUUGAGCAUUGUAUUUCUCGCAUCCCUUCUCGUGAGCGCUUAGACCUUUUUCUAUUUUAGUCGGAUUUUGUUUUGGAAUUUUGCUUUUGUAUGAACACUCAGCAGAAAAGUACUUACUUCUUGCCAGUUAUCUAUUAACCAAAACCUUUGAUUUGUAGUUUUAAAGAUUAACCCUCAAAGUUCUCUUCAUAACUGCCUUGACAUUUUGGGUUGUUCUGUUCUGUUAAUUUUCUUUUGCUUUUUUGUGUUUUUUGUUUGUUUUUACUUUUGCAUUUAAGACCAUUAAAUUUGAUUUUGUUUUGCUCGAAUUUUGUUUUGUUUUUUAUUUUACCUUUUCUUUCUUUUUGGCUAGGGAAGGUGCAGGUGGCCCAGCAUUCAGGGAGGAGUCGUAAGAUCUUAAGAAACCAAUCCUUGCCUCAAGCAAAAGCAUUUCUGAAUCUGUGACGCAAGAAUGUGCAGUUACAGGCUGGUGGCUUUUAAACCAGGAGCCCGGAGGAAGGGUGAAAGAGAAAGCCUGUGAAAUAGGCAGGGCCAGAUCACCCAAAACUCCUCAGGACUGGGAUCUGGCGUUUAUAAAUAACUAGUUUACAGAGAGAAUCACAAACAGGAUAACUUAGUACCAGCAGUUUUUAACCUUGACGUGAGACUAAAACGUGACCGUAGGCUGUUUUUUAGUUAUUGCUCUCAUGAGAUGAUGGCUGUAUUUAUCUGUUUAUUUAUACCUAUUUAUGUAUUUAUUUAUUGAAGUGUGAAAUUGAGCAAUAGGCAGGCACCACCGUCCCCAGAGCAGGUCAGCGUCUCGAGAGGCCCCUGGACAAUUGAGGAUGCCCAUCCCCUCCCCUUUCCCUGAUCUUUUACUGAGGGGCUGUGUGCGCGAUCCUUGCAAAUUGAUGAUGUUGCCAUCCGUACCCAGGCUGUGUCUCAUAAAAGUCGGCCUGGUGCCAGAGAGGACCUCCUUUCUCCCACAGAAUCCCAGAUCCUCAGGAAAAGCCAAAACCGAGGCCCAUUGCCCGGAUUCGACACAAAAGAGGGUCCCUGCUCUGUUGCCCGAGAGCAGUCUGCAUCCUGGGACCAGAAUGCUUUCCUGGAAAAAGAAGCCUUUCAGGUUUCCCUGGGCCAGCAUCUUCUGAUGGAAGGUGGGAGCCAACACCCUUCUGAUGGAAGGUGGGAGCCAACACCCUUCUGAUGGAAGGUGGGAGCCAACACCCUUCUGAUGGAAGGUGGGAGCCAACACCCUUCUGAUGGAAGGUGGGAGCCAACACCCUUCUGAUGGAAGGCGGGAUUCCCGCUUCUGAAACUCCCCCUGGAGUCUCACUCCCACACAUGCCCAUAGCUAGCAUUCAACAGAGAACUCUGUCUUAAGCUUCAACUGUGAAAAUGAUGACGGGCUUGUAGCACCUCAGCUUCUUUCCUCGCCCCCUUUUAUCUGAAUCCUAUCAAUUAUUCUGAUGCUGGGACAGGUGAGAAGAAACUGUGAAGUAUAUGAGCCUUUGAAAGUUCCCUGAAGUUUCUCAGUUCAGGAACAUUCUCAUUGUAUGUGGUCUCCGCUGUUUGAACAGCCUUCUAGCUAAAAAAUUCCAAAGCCUUUAUUUGGGAGUCUUAGCUUGCAAGCUUGUGGAAGGAUUUAGCUUAACAACUGUCACUCCUGAAAAGCAAUCUCUGUUCCAUCAAGGUUCUAGUUGCUGGCCCUGUGUCCUCAAAGUUCAUUACAUCUUAUCAAGGCCUGUUUGCAAAGGGGAGAUCCCUUUUCUUAAAAAAGGCUCAACCCAAAAGAAACCAUUUCUUAAAAAAUUUUACAUAGAUCAGUUGUAUUUCUAUUUAGCAAAAAUGAGUGCUCUGCUUUUAUUUGGGAAUUUCGAUGAAAAAGCGUUCAGAGUAGAUAAUGUUCAUUUAUCAAAAAUCUGGUUUGGGAAAUACCAAAGAGGCUUUGAUUGAAUUCCCUUUUGACCCGUGUGUAACUUCCUCUGGUAGUUAGACCCCAGGCAGCUCCGAAUUUGUGAACCUGCUUCCUGAUGAAUUCUCCCUUGUUCCCCCUUGGCUCUGCCAUUAUUUCGUUUUCAGUGUAAUUUGCCAAGCCGCAGUUUUCUGUGCUGGCUGUGCCUCUAGUCGCAGCUCUGUGACUGAUUCCCUCCCGGGUGCUGAGUCCCCUCCCCGGCCACCAUCCUGCGUGAAUAUCCUGAAAUUCAUGGGCUUCCUCGGGGGCCCGCCCGCAGGUGGUGCUGGGUGGGUUCCGCCACCUUCUCCUGGAAGGUGAGCCUUUUCCUGGCCAAGGGCAGCUGCCUUAACCUCUGAGAGUCUGCGCUUGGCCUUAGUCCUGGAGACCCAGCCUCCAGGGACUGAACCGUGCUGCUGUUGGGAGCCAAGACCGGCCCUUUGGAGCCGGCAGCCCAGGGGUCCCUGCUGGAUCAGAGAAAUAGAAGCACCCGAAGACGGUUAGUGGCAAUUCCUUGACCCGGUUUGCUUCCAAAUGAAGGCCAUUUGUCCACCAGGCAUUGAAAAGACAUGACUUACCCAGUCCGGCAUCGGACUUGAAAAAUCGAAAUUGACAUCACUCAGCUGUUACAUUUCACAUCCGAUUCAGCCCCCUUUUAUUUCCAUGUGCUUUUCGCAGCCUUCCUGUGUUGGAUGAAAGAGAAUAAGAAUUCAGCUGACAGGAGGCCUCUAUCCUGUCCCUCCACCCCACCCUCCACCUCAAUCCCCUCCCAUCUUCCCCAGACCUACCUCACCUACUAGGACCUGAGGCAGCUCCUUAGCAGAGACCCCUGGGGUUUAGCUGACUCUGGGGGUCAGGGGUUCCUGUCCCCAAACUUCGCAAGACAGCCCUGAAGUCACAAGUGCUUUCUUUUAAGUGGCAUUGGCAAUUGGCGUGUAAUGAUGGCAGUAGAAUCUGAAUCUCGGAUCCCAGGCAGGGUUCACAUUUCCAAACCUUUUUGAUUUCCCCUGACCUCUAAUGGCUGGAUCCUAUUUUUCUACAACCUUUCAGUGACAUCGUUCAGGUUUCUUUCUUGGCCAUUUAAAAAAACAAAUUUUUUUUUUCUCACUUGUAAGUCACCGCCAGUACCUAAGUUAGGCUAACGGAGACUUUGACAGGACUGGAUUUUUCUUCCACCAGAAGAGAAGCCUUUUCCGUUGGUUUGGGGCCACCUCUUUGACCAUGACCAUGUGAUGUUCCGUUUACAGUGACUUGCUUUGGGGGAGGGGAGGCUCUCUUAACCGAUUCCCAUGUUGUACAGUAGAUGGUUAGACCUUUUGUAUAUUAGUGUGUUUUAAGUUAUUGAUUUGUUUUAUAUAAAAUAAUUUAUUUUUCAGGUGCCAUUUUUCAUUUUAACUUUGUUUUUACAUGGGUUUGUUUUCAAUAAAGUCUGACACUGGUGUCCAAAAGUCAACAAUAAAAUGAAUCCCAUUGUGUUCUUUUGAAGAUGCCUAUGUAACUUUUAAGCUUUUUAAAUUAUUUUCAGAAAAAAAAAAAGAAAAGCCCUUAUCAGUUUUCCAUCAGCCCAUUGCCUUUUUAUUUUUUUUUUUUAAUCCUUGUGAAUAAAUGUUCUUUAGUGUUUUAGGAGGAAAAAGCAAACCUAGAUUUUGAUAACCCAGAAGACUUCAGAUUAAUAAAGAAGCUUUGAAAGAAGACCAUUUUUCAAAAUUUUAGUGAAGUGUGAAUAUUUUUUGUCAAUGGCUUUCUCAAAGAGAAUGAAACUUUUGCACCAUUUUCAGAGUUUUUAUAGAGAUGCCAAAUUGAUAUAUUUACAUGUAAUGGAAACAUGAAAAAGUUUUAUUAAACAAUUGUUCAUAGCUGUGUAGACAUUUUAAUUCAGUUUCCAAAGCUCUCAAAAAAUCGUAUUUUUGAAGUACGGAGUGAUGCGGUUUGGGGCGUGGCUUACAGUUCCAACGACUCAAUUGUCCCGAUACUCAGUUCUUUCUACAGGUAUCAGGUUCGUGUUAAACGCUGUAUGUUAACUAUGACUGGAAUUCUGUGAUAUUUUGGUAAUAAAUGAAGUGGGAUCAUUGCGA